AGUCCCGCGGUCCUCGUCGCGACCGGCCCGGGCCGCAGGACGCCGCGCUCGGGGGAGCUGAGCCACCUCUCCGCCAGGCCCGUGCGAGCGGGUGAGCGGGCCCCCCGGGCCCCACUGCCUCGGACGCGUCCCCUCCUCGCCCAGUCCCCUCUAGCGCUGUCGCAGACCUCCUGCCAGGGCCCCAGGUCUCCUCCCGCCUGGGCGGGCUCAGUGGCGGUGAGGAUCUAGAAAAGUCUUCCUGUCCUGGUUCUGGGCUGCCCCGGGGCCUGGGGUGAUGACCCGCAAGCCCAAGGGCGCUCGGACUCCUGGCCCGAAAUUCCAGGGCGGACACAGCCCGGGAUCCCAGCAGCCCCAACUCGGAGGAGCUCUGCCCCGGGGAGGGAGGGACAGCGGAGUGGAAACCAGAUUCCGGGGCAGCACUGCGGGGAUGGGCAGGGCGAGAGUACGGCAUGAGGUCCCAGUUGCCUGUCCCAAACCCUUGCUGGUUUUGCAGUGAAUAUGGGGGGAUAAGGGGAAGGGAGAGAGUGAUUUGCCCCAGCCACCCCACCUCUGGGGCUGCCUCCCUCCUCCCUAGGCCAACCACAGGGUUGAGGGUUCCUCAGCCCCAAGCUCAAGCCUGCCCUUGCUGCUCUCUGCUGGACGGGAGCCCUUCUGCUGCCUGCCUGGGUCCAGGGCUCCAGCCCAGGAGCCUACUUGAUAUGGGAAGGAGGGAGGGGUCCCCAGGGCCUGCCUCAUUUCCAGCCCGGGGCUCUCCCACCAUGGGAGAAGAGCUGGGAAGAAGAAGAGGAGGCCCCCUCGACUCUGGACACCAGGCCCCUAACACGAGACCCCUGGAUGAGAGCAUCCGCUCUCCCGUGACCAGGCGUUCGAGCUCCAGGGGCAGGGAAAGGAUUCCCAGGGCCUAGUGAGGCCCCUGUUAUCAGAUGAGGCGCCCUGAAAACAUAGGCUGGGCUUGUGUGAGAUGGGAGAAAGACCAGAAGUAUCGUCUAAACUUCUCCCUGCCCACACAUCCAGCUUCAUGGCACUGUGCUACAAAGCUGGUCUCAUUGGGCCUAGGGGUCUUUGAGAGCUGAGCUUGGCAGCCCCUGGGGCCCAACCUCACCCCUAGUCCCAGCAAGUGAGAGCGAAGCAUCUUGCCCUGUCUACCUCCUUGCCCAAAGCACACACCAGGCAGUGACCAUGACUCAUGGUUCCCAGUACAAAGAAAAGAGCACUUCCCUGCUGGGGCAGAGGCCAAGCCAGAGCCCUGGCCCCAUCACCUCUCUGCCCUGCUUGAGUCUGGAAUGGACCUCCCUGCCUGGAAGCUGCAUUGCCCUUGGUCCUGGGCCUGCCUGCCCCCUGGGGAACACAGGCAGCAGCCACAUUGGCAGUGAGGCCGUGGCAGCGUCGGCAGCAGAGGAUGCCCCAGGCCCUGGAGCGUGCAGAUGGCAGCUGGGCCUGGGUGGUGCUGCUGGCCACCAUGGUGACCCAGGGCCUCACCCUGGGCUUCCCCACGUGUAUCGGCAUCUUCUUCACUGAAUUGCAAUGGGAGUUCCAGGCCAGCAACAGCGAGACCUCUUGGUUCCCCUCCAUCCUCACGGCUGUGCUCCACAUGGCAGGGCCCCUGUGCAGCAUCCUGGUGGGACGCUUCGGCUGCCGAGUGACCGUGAUGCUGGGGGGCGUGCUGGCCAGCCUGGGCAUGGUGGCCAGCUCCUUCUCUCACAACCUCAGCCAGCUCUACUUCACAGCAGGAUUCAUCACAGGCCUGGGCAUGUGCUUCAGCUUCCAGUCAAGCAUCACGGUGCUGGGCUUCUACUUUGUCCGCCGGCGGGUGCUGGCCAACGCGCUGGCCUCGAUGGGCGUCUCCCUGGGCAUCACCCUCUGGCCGCUGCUCUCCCGCUACCUUCUGGAGAACCUGGGCUGGAGGGGUACCUUCCUUGUCUUCGGCGGGAUCUUUCUCCACUGCUGCAUCUGCGGGGCCAUCAUAAGGCCUGUGGCCACCAGUGUGGCCCCUGAGACCAAAGAAUGUCCCCCGCCACCUCCCGAGACACCUGCACUUGGCUGCCUGGCUGCAUGCGGCCGGACCAUCCAGCGCCACCUGGCCUUCGACAUCCUGCGGCACAACACAGGCUACUGCGUGUACAUACUGGGUGUGAUGUGGUCCGUCCUGGGCUUCCCACUGCCACAAGUCUUCCUGGUGCCAUAUGCCAUGUGGCACAGCGUGGACGAGCAGCAGGCAGCCCUCCUCAUCUCCAUCAUCGGCUUCAGCAACAUCUUCCUGAGGCCCCUAGCCGGGCUGAUGGCAGGACGGCCGGCCUUUGCUAGCCACCGCAAGUACCUGUUCAGCCUGGCACUCCUGCUCAAUGGGCUCACUAACCUGGUGUGUGCGGCAUCAGGUGACUUCUGGGUGCUCGUGGGCUACUGCCUGGCGUACAGCGUGUCCAUGAGUGGCAUCGGCGCCCUCAUCUUCCAGGUUCUCAUGGACAUCGUCCCCAUGGAUCAGUUCCCCAGAGCCCUGGGACUCUUCACUGUCCUGGACGGCCUUGCUUUCCUCAUCUCCCCACCACUGGCCGGGUUGCUCCUGGACGCCACCAACAACUUUAGCUAUGUUUUCUACAUGUCCAGCUUCUUCCUCAUCUCAGCUGCCCUCUUCAUGGGUGGCAGCUUCUACGCCCUGCAGAAGAAGGAGCAAGGCAAGCAGGCUGUCGCGGCGGAUGCCCUGGAGCGGGAUCUUUUCUUGGAAGCCAAAGACGGUCCUGGGAAGCAACGGUCCCCUGAGAUCAUGUGCCAGUCUUCCCGCCAGCCACGUCCAGCUGGCGUCAAUAAGCAUCUUUGGGGAUGUCCUGCCUCCUCCAGGACCAGCCAUGAGUGGCUCUUAUGGCCAAAGGCGGUACUGCAGGCCAAGCAAACGGCUCUGGGCUGGAAUAGCCCUACCUGAGUGCCCUGUUUGACUCCGCCACUAUCUGCCAUGUGAGUUGGGCAAAUUGUUGACCACCUCUGAGCCUUGAAAAAGUAGGAGGUUACUUUGUUAGAGCAAAAUAAUAAAAUUUAAUUUUAAAAAAGAAAA